GUCUAGAGCGGCGGCGGCUGGCUAGGGCUGCGGCGCGCGUGGAGGGUUCGCUGCUGGUUUGCCGCCGGGUCGGGCUCCGUGGGCCGGGGCAGGAGGACCAGCACCUGAGGCCGGGCCCGCAGCCCGCGACUUCACAGCCAGGCGGCGGCGCUGCUGCUGCUGCGGGGCUCUGGCGCGCAGCCCGGCGGGACAGCGGGGCGGCUGGCGCCGGGGGCCGGGGAGCGCCAGAUGAUGGAUUUGGACAUGCUUCUAUGAAGAAAUGCCACAUGGUCCGAGAGCAAACAUGUCCAGGCUACUGCCACUUUAGUGGACUAGGGCUCGGUGCCAGCACUUCCCGGGUAAUCAGGCGUGGUCUGACCGAGGAUCAAGAAGCACAUCAUCACCAAUGACAUCAUGACAGCAAGAGAGCACAGCCCUCGCCAUGGUGCCAGGGCCCGUGCAAUGCAGCGGGCUUCCACCAUCGACGUGGCGGCCGACAUGCUGGGCCUCUCUCUGGCAGGAAAUAUACAAGACCCAGAUGAGCCCAUUUUAGAAUUUAGCUUAGCUUGCAGUGAGCUGCAUACUCCAUCGCUAGAUCGAAAGCCAAAUAGUUUUGUUGCGGUGAGUGUCACCACCCCUCCUCAGGCAUUCUGGACGAAGCAUGCACAGACGGAGAUCAUUGAGGGAACCAACAAUCCUAUAUUUCUAAGCAGUAUUGCCUUCUUUCAAGACUCUCUUAUCAAUCAGAUGACACAAGUCAAACUCUCCGUGUAUGAUGUCAAAGAUAGAUCUCAGGGAACAAUGUAUUUACUGGGCUCUGGAACGUUCAUUGUCAAAGAUCUGCUCCAGGACAGGCAUCAUAGGUUGCAUUUAACACUAAGGUCUGCAGAGAGUGACCGUGUAGGUAACAUCACCGUGAUUGGCUGGCAGAUGGAGGAGAAGUCAGACCAACGGCCCCCUGUGACCCGGUCUGUGGACACUGUCAAUGGGAGGAUGGUUCUUCCUGUCGAUGAGAGCUUGACGGAGGCGUUAGGAAUCCGAUCCAAAUACGCUUCAUUGCGAAAGGACACUUUGCUGAAAUCGGUGUUCGGUGGUGCCAUCUGCCGCAUGUACCGGUUUCCAACCACUGAUGGUAACCAUUUGCGGAUCCUGGAGCAGAUGGCAGAGAGCGUGCUCUCCCUGCACGUGCCCCGGCAGUUCGUGAAGCUCCUACUAGAGGAAGAUGCAGCCAGAGUGUGUGAGCUGGAGGAGCUGGGAGAGCUGUCCCCUUGCUGGGAGAGCCUCCGGCGCCAAAUUGUCACCCAGUACCAGACCAUCAUCCUCACAUACCAGGAGAACCUGACCGACCUCCAUCAGUACAGAGGGCCCUCGUUUAAAGCAAGCAGUUUGAAAGCAGAUAAAAAGUUAGAAUUUGUUCCCACAAACUUGCACAUACAAAGGAUGAGAGUUCAAGACGAUGGAGGAUCAGAUCAGAACUACGACAUCGUCACCAUUGGGGCGCCAGCAGCACACUGCCAAGGUUUUAAGUCAGGAGGUCUCCGCAAAAAGCUGCACAAAUUUGAAGAGACCAAGAAACACAGUUUUGAGGAGUGUUGUACAUCAUCUGGCUGCCAGUCCAUAAUCUACAUACCCCAGGAUGUUGUCAGAGCCAAGGAGAUCAUCGCCCAGAUCAACACCCUGAAAACCCAAGUGAGUUACUACGCAGAGCGGCUGUCAAGGGCAGCCAAGGACAGGUCUGCCACUGGCCUUGAGAGGACACUCGCCAUCUUGGCAGACAAGACACGGCAGCUGGUCACGGUCUGCGACUGCAAGCUCCUGGCCAACUCCAUCCAUGGGCUGAACGCUGCACGGCCUGACUACAUUGCCUCCAAGGCCUCUCCCACUUCGACUGAGGAGGAGCAGGUGAUGCUUAGAAAUGACCAGGACACCCUCAUGGCCCGGUGGACAGGGAGAAACAGCCGAUCUUCCCUGCAGGUGGACUGGCACGAGGAGGAGUGGGAGAAAGUGUGGCUGAACGUGGACAAGAGCCUAGAGUGCAUCAUUCAGCGUGUGGACAAGCUGCUGCAGAAGGAGCGGCUGCAUGGCGAGGGCUGUGAGGAUGUCUUCCCCUGUGCAGGCAGCUGCACCAGCAAGAAAGGUAACCCGGACAGCCACGCCUACUGGAUCAGACCAGAAGACCCCUUCUGUGAUGUCCCCUCCUCACCAUGCCCCUCCACCAUGCCCUCCACUGCAUGCCAUCCUCAUCUGACCACACAUUGCAGUCCCCCUCCUGAAGAGUCCAGCCCAGGUGAAUGGAGUGAGGCCCUUUACCCGCUGCUGACCACUCUCACCGACUGCGUGGCCAUGAUGAGUGACAAGGCCAAGAAGGCCAUGGUAUUCCUGCUCAUGCAGGACAGCGCGCCCACCAUAGCCACCUACCUGAGCCUGCAGUACCGCCGUGACGUGGUCUUCUGCCAGACGCUGACCGCCCUCAUCUGCGGCUUCAUCAUUAAGCUGAGGAACUGCCUGCAUGACGACGGCUUCCUGCGCCAGCUCUACACCAUCGGGCUGCUGGCCCAGUUCGAGAGCCUGCUGAGCACCUACGGGGAGGAGCUGGCAAUGCUGGAGGACAUGAGCCUUGGGAUCAUGGACUUGAGGAACGUGACCUUCAAAGUCACUCAGGCCACUUCCAGCGCCUCCGCAGACAUGCUGCCCGUCAUCACAGGAAAUCGCGACGGGUUUAACGUGCGGGUCCCUCUGCCGGGCCCGCUGUUUGACGCCUUGCCCCGGGAGAUCCAGAGUGGCAUGCUGCUGCGAGUGCAGCCCGUCCUCUUCAACGUGGGCAUCAAUGAGCAGCAGACACUGGCCGAGAGGUUUGGCGAUACGUCUUUACAAGAAGUCAUCAACGUGGAGAGUUUGGUGCGGUUAAAUUCCUACUUUGAGCAGUUUAAGGAAGUUUUGCCUGAGGAUUGCCUGCCUCGGUCUCGCAGUCAGACGUGCCUGCCAGAGCUGCUGCGGUUUCUGGGUCAGAACGUGCAUGCCCGGAAGAAUAAGAACGUCGACAUUCUCUGGCAAGCUGCUGAGAUCUGCCGCCGCCUUAAUGGGGUCCGGUUCACCAGCUGCAAGAGCGCUAAGGACCGUACAGCCAUGUCGGUGACACUGGAGCAGUGCCUGAUCCUGCAACACGAGCAUGGCAUGGCCCCGCAGGUCUUCACCCAGGCCCUGGAGUGCAUGCGCAGUGAGGGUUGUCGAAGAGAAAAUACAAUGAAGAAUGUUGGAAGUCGCAAAUAUGCAUUUAAUUCCCUGCAGCUGAAGGCUUUCCCCAAGCAUUACAGGCCUCCCGAAGGGACUUACGGAAAAGUUGAAACGUGAACACACGGUUUCCUCUAAUUAGCUGUUACAUAAUAAAUGUGGGUACCCUCUAGUGUCAUAUAUGAAUUCUUCAAGAAGACCUGAAGGAUUGGUUUUUAUUUUUUGUGGUUUUUUUAAAAAAAACAUUUCACUAAAGAGUCUCUGGAGCAUGUUUUUUGUUUUUUGGGUUUUUUUCCCCAUUGGAAUCAAUAGGAGGUAAUGUUUGGCUCAAUAGUGUGGAUAGUAACAACUGCCUAUUUAAAUUAAAUAGCCUUUGGCUGUAACUACACAGAUCUCAUCAAUAGUUACCUACAUGAAUCAAGCUAGGUUUGUCUGAAAUGCUAGAAGACUUUUUCAAAUGCCUGCUUGCUCACUUACUUUUCUACAGAGUAACUCAAAAGUAACCAUUGAAUUACAAUCCACUUUGUAAAAAUCUGAAUGUAAAACAGUAAAUAAUAAAUUAAAUAAUUGGAUCCUAGGCAUACCAAUAAAUGUUAUUUGGGGAAAGAAGCUAGCACUAUCUCAUGCAGUGAGAAUAACGGGUUCUAGUGAAUUAUCCUAUCUACACUACCACCUGAAGAAGUUGAAAGAAAGAUUGAUAAAUCAACGGGAGAUAAGACUUUAUUAGAAGGUAACACCUGCAAGGUACCCCACAUAGUUGGGGCCACUCUUUUUUCUGUCCCUUAUGAGUUACAGAACAGGGAGUCUGCUGGAGACACAAAGCCAGCAGUAAGGUCCCUUUAGCCUGUCUCCUGUUCUCUGAAGCUCCCUGCCGAGGCUCCCUCACGCCCAGAGGACACAUCUCCCCUUCUUCUCUAGAUGUUAAUGUAGGGCCUCAGAUGUGGCAUGUCAACACUCCCAUGGGGAAUUUAUGACCAUAGAGAUAGUAGAAACCUAAAUAUUUUCAGAAAAAAAAUUUUUUUUGCAGGAUUUCCAAUUUAUCUUUGAAAAGACAGUACAAUCAUGUUUGAAUGUCUGAUGAAAGUGUCUUAUUUUUAGGUUUGCAAUAAUUGUUACUUUCUUAUUCUCAUUCUUAUGUAAGAUGACUAUUGAGAAACAGUUGAAAUUUAUUCUCCUCAAAUGAGAUUUUGAAAGGGAUUUAUGGGCCAUAAAACUUAGGAAUUUCAUAGAAAAUUUUGUCUGGUCAUCUUUUAUAAGAUGAUGAUGAGUCUUAUCUGCACAUAGCAGAGUUUGUUUCUUAGGAGUUUAUAUGUUUUAUUGAUUCUGUUUACGAUGUUUACAUGUUCUUGAAAAGGUUGUAAAAGAAAUACAUAUGGCACAUAUUAAUGAUGCUGAUCCUAAUGAUUUGUGAACCUCUUAGAAAUUCUUUUGUCUAAAAGCCUAGAGAUUCUUCUGGUUCCUUUAGAAACAUGUAACAAACUUGGGCCAGGGGUGCUGAGGCAUGGGGAGGACUGCUUAUUGGCAGGAACACAGAGGGGGUGGGCAUCAGGUAGGGUGGAACUGGAUGACCUUCCAGACCCCCUCCUACUCAGAAGUCAGCAUGCAAGCAGCGCCUGCUGUCUCCCGAUGCCUGCAGGGAGGAAAAUGUCUGUGAAGGACACUUUAAUGAAGGACGAAGCUCUCUGCUGCUCCCUCAAAGCUGAGUUCACUGUGGCAGGCAGGAAGCAGAGAAGCUCCUGCCCGCCAAACCCACUGCACAGGUGGCUGCUGCUGGUAUCAGAUUCUCCUUUUUAAGUGUCAAUUUCUGUUCACAGACAGUUUGUUUUCAAUAUGGCUGAUUUACCCUUUCACCUCUCCACCAUCUCAUUUAAUUUGUAAAUUUUUAGUUCUGUCUUUUCUCAUUUUAACUUUUAAAAAAUCUCCUUGCUUUUUAAAAAUAAAUAUUACCCACAUAGUUUUCAGAUCUUUUUUGUCUGGAGAGCAUUAAAUAUCUGCACUCAUCAAAGGGAAUAUAGCAAAUGUUGAUCAUCUGUCAGCAGUUUUGCAUGUGACACCUUUAUAUGAAUUAUUUUCCCAAUUUUUGCUCUAUGUAAUGGGUCACCAUAAAACUGUAAGACUUGGCAAAUGCUAUAGAAAAGGUUCAGGUUUCAGUAUUCUCUCUGAAGGCAUCAUUCCUGGGCUUCCGGCAGCAUCACACGCUUCCAGUGCCUGCAGGGUGAGGGUGUGUGGCACAGAGGCAAGCAGCUCCUCUCUUCUGUAGGAGCUUUGGGUUUUCAGAGGUGCAGGGAAGGCAGUUUUACAGGUUACCGUAAAACAGAGGUUCCGUCCAGUGUUCCUUAUGAUGCCUCCCCAUUUAAAAAGAAAAGAGAUCUAUGGAAAACUGGGAAUGUAAUGUGGAUUCUGUCAGAGCUCCUACAGAGCACAGUUGCCUUUAGUUUCCUUUAAAGAUGUAAAAAUAUUGUAUAAUACAGUUUUGUCCCUACACAAUUGUAUUUGCCAAGCUUAGUGCAUUAUGAUACCUUUAUUUAUUUGUUUUGGGCAGUAUUACUAUAUAUAUAUAAACAUACAGUUACUGUUUUAUAUAUUCUUAGGUCAUUCAAAGCCAUGUAUGCUGUAAAUGUGCUAGUCUUUAGAAUGACACAUAAUAAAUAACUGACAAGAUAUUAAAUGUGGUCUUGCCUGAUUCAUCCUAUUAGGAGGACUAGUUCUAUGUGACCAGCCUGUGACUGGACCAUUGUUCUUGGGCAUUGCAUUGAGUGCUCGGGUGCUGAAUACAUGUUUGUAAACAUGGGACCAUGGGAGACUUCCAUUUUAUAAGCUUGUUUCUGCCUAAUUUGAAGCAGAGGGGCAACAGCGUUGAGGUUAAGAGCACGGACUUUGGGAGCACACAGACCAGGUCCCAAUCCUGGUUCUGCCCCUGACUGGCUGGUGACUCUGAGCAAGUUGCUUGACCUCUCCAAGCCUCCGUUUCCUCAUGUGCAAAGUGUGGACAACAACAGUACCUUCCUCAUAAGGAACGUGCGACGCGCCUCAGAAGUACGUGUUCAUAAAUGGUAGCCAUUGUUGUUACCUUCCCGUCUGUGAACAUGGAUCACAUCAUCUCUGUGGGUAACCCAGUCCUCGUUGUAUGACUUGUCAAAAUGCAGUUCCACUUGUAUUAAUAUUGACCCUGUUCAUCGUCACCAGGACUGCAUCUUGCACCACUGUGCCGUCUUCUAGGCACACACGACCCGUUAUCUCCCUUGGAAAAAUUCCUCUCACUGGAAAUGUACAAUUAAAGGAUGAUUGAAAUGUUUAACUCUUGGAGUUUUUAGUAUUACCAAACUCCUAGAAAUUUAAGCUACCACCAAAAAUAACAUGUGCCUUUUCCCUUUAUUCUCAUUGAUGGUAGCAGUGCACCUCGUUUCAGUGUCCUGAUUCCUUGAUUACUGUGAACACUGAACAUCUUUUAUACCUUUAUGAUAUUUCUAUGUUUGUGACUUCAUUGGAAUGUUGAUCUAUUUCAUAUAGAUUGUUUUUAAUAUACAAUGUAUUAGCCCCUGUCAUAUGUUGCACACUUUUUAACCUAUUUGUCAGCUGUCUUUUGGUCUGUGGUAGGAGUUAUACAGUAUUUUAAAUGGUUUAUGUAGUCACAUAUACCUGUCUUUCAUUUUGAUGCUUGUUCUGAAAUGGAGUCCUGGCUUCACCAUGGAAGGUGGGACAUAUGGGACAGCCAUGUCCUUGUGGGCAUGGUGGUGUGGCUGCGUGCCCACGACGAGGGGCUGGACUAAAGUGCUCACUGGCACCUUGCUUGGUGCAUGGGCCAUGCUCAGUUUAAUAUUAUUAACAGUUUCUACCUUCACUCUCAUGUCUCAGGAUUAUUUUUUCAGCAUUUACCUGUUCUUAUUUCUAGGAUGUUUAUGGUUUCAGUCCUACAUUUAGAUCAAUCCAUCUGGAAUCAUCUUGGUGUAAGUCCUGUGUUGUGCUUACAGUAUGUAAAGUCAGAGGGAAUCCCUCAAGGUCAGGCCUAAUUUUGCUUCUCUUUAAAGUUAAGCCAAGAAGAAGACAUGUCAGGACGCCCAGACAUCAGCUACCGUGAGCUUCUUCCUGCCCUCCCUCCGCAUGCCAUUCUGGUGCUGCGCUUCAGUUUCCUGUUGAGUCUCUGCUUAGUAGAUGACUUGGCACAAUCUGGCUGCCCAGAUCUAGGGGAGUUGUCCCAGGGAGGCUUUGCGCUGGAGGAAGGUAAGAGGAGCUGGAGGUUGGAGCUUCCCGAUUUGUGAUUUUUCCAAGAACAGAAAUGAUUAGCCAUGUGGGGAGGUUACUUCAUUGUACAUUGUUCUACUGCAUAACCUCCCUCUAUUCUUUACCAGCAUCACACAGCAGGUUGGCACCAUUUUUGAAUAGAGGUUUCUCACAGUAUCCUCAGCAGCAUUGAGUGUUCCUAAUGUUGUAGUAAUGAGCAGUAGAUGUCUCUCAGUGGGCAGUGUGACCUCUUUGGUCACUCUAAAGGGCUGCCAGCAUUUCUCUUAAGCUGGGGGGAGAAGAGCUGUUCUGUGUAUAGGGGUAUUGGGAACACAUGGACAGAAGGAACUGGCCUCACAUGCCAUCGUGUUCCUGGGAUGGCUCUUCCAAGACCAGCAGUUCCUCCUGGCAGGCAGGCCCUCACAGAACUCUGCAUUUGGAGAUGGACAAACUCUCUUCUUCUUAUCACUUUCUCCCCAAAAUGUCCUCUUCUACCAGCCCCUCUUAAGAGCCGAUUUUCUGUAAGUUAUAGUGAGGGCACUGCUCUGCUGUGCACAGAAGGAACCCCAGCCCAGAAGCACACGCUCCCUGUGGAACCUGCAGGGGUGGCAGUGAUGACAGAACCAAGGGGGUCAAGGAAGAUUGGAGAGGAGUGGGCAGCAGGAAACAGCUCAGGCUGCCUGACCUGGCCCCCGGCUGCCCAUGAGGGCCUCCAGAGAGGGGCAGAGCUGGCUUAUCGGGAUCCAUGAUGGUUUUUACACUUUUAAAAGUGCCCUCUUCUCAGAGACCCUGGUUAUUUCCAAAAGUAGGAAGUAAUCAAAUUUACAGUGGAUAAAAUCCAGUAUUUGAAAUCAGGAAGACAGAAAAAAAAGCAAAAUAGCAUCCUUUUCUGAGAGGUAUAUGCUGACCAAAAAGAUCUUUCAUUCCUGUGAACACCAAGCAGCGCGGCCUCUGGCAGAGAGAGCGCUGGGUUGUACAGAUGGAAACUUGUGUUUAGCAGGCUGUCUGCUCCCAAUAGUGGCCCUGGCUGCAACUGACCUCCUGAUGCCCUGCUGACGCUAACUGUGGGUACCAACCAGCACCGUGGACAUCGGCCCCAGGAUCAGUCUACGAUUUGUCUGGUGGCCAAAUGAUGACUUUUGAGUGGGAAAAGCUGGUGGGGGCUACACCGUGCUCUGCAGUGUAGUGGGAUCCUGUGAGCUGGCCUGCACAGGCACUCCCUCCCCUGCCAGGGGCCCCAGGGAGGCUUCUCCAGCCUGAGGCUGCACCCUCCAUACGAUUCCACCCCCCAUCCUGUGCCAACAGUAGGCAAACGGAGAGUAGCUUGGUCUUGUUUUUAUUAGCUGUUGCCCUCCAGGCUACGACAGGGUUCCCAGGGUGUAGCCUGAAAACACCCAUACUCUAGAUUCCCUCCACUGGAACCCUGUCUUUGCCAUGAUUUCUUCCUGCAUCAGGCCCCUGUGGGCCUUGCAGGCCAGUCCAGGCAGGUCUUUCACACUGUUGUCCCACAUAACAGAAAAAGCUGAGCAGACAGGGUAGGAAACACACUUGCAUCUCCAUGGCUCCAAAGAGGAUGCCUGUGUUAGAUGGAUGUAGACAGACACAGCACUUCACUGCUUCCUCCUCCUCGCCACCCAGCCCUCCCUCGGUGUCUGUGGCCUGACUCUCUCCUGGUGGUCCUACGUCUCUGACCAUCCCUCCUCACUCUCAAAUUUUAUGUUGCCCACCACCUGCCACUAAUGGCGUGGUGUUCUCCUGGGUUCCCUUUCUCACUUAAGAUGAUCUUCCUGAAAAAUCUUACACAUUCCUGUUGAACAAAUGGUCACUUAUAUGGUAGUGACUCCUAAAUUUCUAGGUCCAUCCCAGACUCUCCCCCAAGGUCCAGAUUACCUAUACAUCUAAGCACCAUGCCUGUCUUGCAGGCAUCUCAAAUACAGCAUGCUCAUGCCUCUCCUCCUCCAAGCUGGCUGAGUCUCCCUCUAAUAGACGACCUUGGGAUCAUUUUCUCCUCCACAUCCCAUCAAUCAGCCACUGAACCUGUAUCUCUUGAGAACCAUCCCAUAAUUUCCAUCCAUGCACCCCAAGGCCUGGUCUGUAUCAGUCCCCUCGGAUCUGGACCUCUCCUGAGCAUCCUCACCCCUCCUGCAAGGCUAGUCUCAGGUCUGCCUUCCUCUAUGGUGAUUUCUCCCCACAAAUGAAGUUGGCCCUUUCAAAAAAACUUCCUCUCCUUCAUUGUUGACUAUGAAGAUUCUUUCAUGCAUGUCCUGUCCACUGUCAGUCCCCUCUGUAUUCACAAGAGCAAGUGUAAUGCCCGCUGUGAAGGAGCUAAAGUUUGUUGAAUAAACACAUGAACAAAUGGUGGUUUUGUGGUGUUCAACUGAAAUAUUUCCUAUUUCAGCACUGGACCACGCUGUUUUUCUCACUACAUAAUCGGUUACGCUAAAUGCAUCACGAGCCAAAUUCAAAAGGUCAAAGGAGAAGGCAAAUGGCAGAGUGUGGUAAAGGGGCGAGUGAGAGGGUCUCUGAAAAAAGUCAGGCUAAAAUUACAGGGGGUUCAGGCAAUGUUAUCUUGAUCUGGAUGGCCAGUUACAUGACAGAUUACUUUGUUCUUAACAUACGAACAUCCUAUUCACUUUUUGGUAUACUGGUUGUUUAACAGUAAAAAUUAAAUGUUUAAAACCCA